AGAUUUUCCUUAGACAGAAAGGAAAAGAACCUUCCAUUUUUGGCUGUGCCAAGAAGCUCAGAAAGGCGAUAAUAUAAAAAAUAUAUAGUUAAUUGGGAAUUGAAUUUACAAAAUACAUUGUGUGGUGAUGCAAUAGAAAGCUCAUAAUUGGAACGAGAUUGAGAUGGUAUAUUCCCGGAGAGGAAGUCUGGGAUCCCGGCUCCUGCUGCUCUGGCUUCUCCUUGCCUACUGGAAGGCAGGGAGCGGCCAGCUCCACUACUCGAUCCCGGAGGAAGCCAAACACGGAACCUUCGUUGGCCGCAUCGCGCAGGACCUAGGGCUGGAGCUGGCGGAGCUGGUGCCGCGCCUGUUCCGGGUGGCGUCCAAGGGCCGCGGGGACCUUCUGGAGGUAAAUCUGCAGAAUGGCAUUUUGUUUGUGAAUUCUCGGAUCGACCGGGAGGAGCUGUGCCGGCGGAGGGCGGAGUGCAGCAUCCACCUGGAGGUGAUCGUGGACAGGCCGCUGCAGGUUUUCCAUGUGGAGGUGGCAGUGAAGGACAUCAAUGACAAUCCGCCCAGGUUCUCCAGACAAGAACAAAGAUUAUUCAUUUUAGAGUCAAGAAUGCCAGAUUCGCGGUUUCCGCUAGAGGGCGCGUCGGAUUUGGAUAUUGGAGCAAAUGCACAAUUGAGAUACAGGUUAAAUCCAAACGAAUAUUUUGACUUAGAUGUUAAAACAAAUGAAGAAGAAACGAACUUUUUAGAGCUGGUUUUGAGGAAAUCCUUAGAUAGAGAAGAAACACAAGAACACCGUUUAUUAGUGAUUGCAACUGAUGGAGGAAAACCCGAACUAACAGGUACAGUUCAGUUGUUGAUCAAUGUAUUGGAUGCUAAUGAUAACGCCCCAGAAUUUGAUAAAUCCAUUUAUAAUGUCAGAUUGUUGGAAAAUGCACCAAGUGGGACAUUAGUUAUUAAACUGAACGCCUCAGAUGCAGAUGAGGGCAUCAAUAAGGAAAUAGUGUAUUUCUUUAGUAAUCUUGUUCUUGACGAUGUAAAGUCCAAAUUUAUAAUUAAUUCUAAUACUGGUGAAAUAAAAGUUAACGGGGAACUGGAUUAUGAAGACUAUAACUCAUAUGAAAUUAAUAUUGAUGCCAUGGAUAAAAGUACAUUCCCAUUAUCAGGACACUGUAAAGUAGUAGUGAAACUCCUGGAUGUGAAUGAUAAUACCCCAGAGAUGGCCAUAACCACCCUUUUCCUGCCUGUCAAAGAGGACGCUCCACUCAGCACGGUCAUUGCUCUGAUCAGCGUGUCUGACCGUGACUCAGGUGCCAACGGGCAGGUGACCUGCUCCCUAAUGCCCCACGUUCCCUUCAAGCUGGUGUCCACCUUCAAGAAUUACUACUCGUUGGUGCUGGACAGCGCCCUGGACCGCGAGAGCGUGUCGGUCUAUGAGCUGGUGGUGACCGCGCGGGACGGGGGCUCGCCUUCGCUGUGGGCCACCGCCAGCGUGUCUGUGGAAGUGGCCGACGUGAACGACAACGCUCCGGCGUUCGCGCAGCCCCAGUAUACCGUGUUCGUGAAGGAGAACAACCCGCCAGGCUGCCACAUCUUCACGGUGUCUGCACGGGACGCGGACGCGCAGGAGAACGCCCUGGUGUCCUACUCGCUGGUGGAGCGGCGGGUGGGCGAGCGCCCGCUGUCGAGUUACGUUUCGGUGCACGCGGAGAGCGGCAAGGUGUACGCGCUGCAGCCGCUGGACCACGAGGAAGUGGAGCUGCUGCAGUUCCAGGUGAGCGCGCGCGACGCGGGCGUGCCGCCUCUGGGCAGCAACGUGACGCUGCAGGUGUUCGUGCUGGACGAGAACGACAACGCGCCGGCGCUGCUGGUGCCUCGAGUGGGUGGCACCGGCGGCGCAGUGAGCGAGCUGGUGCCGAGGUCAGUGGGUGCGGGCCACGUGGUGGCGAAGGUGCGCGCAGUGGACCCUGAUUCGGGCUACAACGCUUGGCUUUCGUAUGAGCUGCAGCCAGCGCCUGGCAGUGCGCGCAUCCCGUUCCGCGUGGGGCUGUACACAGGCGAGAUCAGCACAACACGCUCUCUGGAUGAGACCGAAGCACCGCGCCACCGCCUUCUGGUGCUGGUGAAGGACCAUGGAGAGCCCCCGCUGACAGCCACAGCCACAGUGCUGGUGUCGCUGGUGGAAAGUGGCCAGGCGCCGAAGGCCUCAUCGCGGGCGUCGGCGGGCGCUGUGGGUCCCGAGGCUGCCCUGGUGGAUGUCAACGUGUACCUGAUCAUCGCCAUCUGUGCGGUGUCCAGCCUGCUGGUGCUCACGCUGCUGCUGUACACCGCGCUGCGGUGCUCGGCGCAGCCCACCGAGGCCGUGUGCACACGGGGCAAGCCCACUCUGUUGUGCUCCAGCGCGGUGGGGAGCUGGUCGUACUCGCAGCAGAGGAGACAGAGGGUGUGCUCUGGGGAAGCUCCACCCAAAACAGACCUCAUGGCCUUCAGUCCAAGCCUUCCUCAGGGUCCCACCUCUACAGACAACCCACGACAGCCCAACCCUGACUGGCGUUACUCUGCCUCCCUGAGAGCAGGCAUGCACAGCUCUGUGCACCUAGAGGAGGCUGGCAUUCUACGGGCUGGUCCAGGAGGGCCUGAUCAGCAGUGGCCAACAGUAUCCAGUGCAACACCAGAACCAGAGGCAGGAGAAGUGUCCCCUCCAGUCGGUGCGGGUGUCAACAGCAACAGCUGGACCUUUAAAUACGGACCAGGCAACCCCAAACAAUCCGGUCCCGGUGAGUUGCCCGACAAAUUCAUUAUCCCAGGAUCUCCUGCAAUCAUCUCCAUCCGGCAGGAGCCUACUAACAGCCAAAUUGACAAAAGUGACUUCAUAACCUUCGGCAAAAAGGAGGAGACCAAGAAAAAGAAGAAAAAGAAGAAGGGUAACAAGACCCAGGAGAAAAAAGAGAAAGGGAACAGCACGACUGACAACAGUGACCAGUGAGGUCCUCAAAUGGAAACAAGCCACUUAGCCAGUUUUUGUAAUAAUGGCAAAUCUCUCCCAUGUAGCAAUUCCCUGCUCCUUUUUCCUAUCUACAUGAGCCCUCUUAGAGACCUCAGAAAUCUGCAGAAAGUUCCCUGUGUCUGUCUAGAACGCAUUUAACAGGUUUUGUCGUAAAAGCUUUACUAAGUCUGGUGUUAACUCUUUCUCUCCACUCUGGCUUGUUUUCAGAACCUAAAAAGCAGACCCAAGUUUCCUUUCUCCUCCGCCGCAAAGGAGAGGCUUCCCAGCCCCGCCAGUGAGAGGUUGGACUCUCUGCCCUGUGCUCCGGGGAUCCUGUCUUGAUGACACUUGCAGGGCAGGCUGAAAAGUUUUGAGAUUGAGCAGCUUGGGAGUUUGUGGCCACUGGGUAUGUGUGGCUACCGCGGGUAUGCGAGUGCCAGAUAUUGGCUGAGACGAGCCAGCUUAGACUAAUUGGUACAAGGAAGGCAAGAAAACAAAGACAAAUAAACAGCGGAAGUUAUCAGUAUGGAGGGGAAGUGUAAACUUAAAGGGACCAGACUUUCUAAAUCUUACAACUCAAGAGGUGGCAGCCACCCUCUAGGAGACAAAACUACCCCCACUGACAAGGCUUUAGGAGACCCUAAAGUCUGUUGGCUGUGACGUCAUUAUACCUAAAAUCUGCAUCAUACCUGCAAGCCAACAGUUCAGUGUUUUAACAGAGAACCACCCUGGGAAACAGAAGCAGAUCUGAUGUGUUUCCUAUACAUGUCCUGUGCUCACUUUAUUAAAAAUUCUUUUGCACACAAUGUUUAUGAAAAGGCCAGAUCCUUUUCCAAUACUUAUGCAAAAGCAAAAGAAAACCCCGACACCUCACCUUUCGCUGUUUGUUGUUUCAUAGAUUUAUUUAAAAAAAGAGAAAGUCUAUAGCUAUAAAUCUUUAAAGAGAAAUAUGAAUACAAUUCCCCUAAACUCUCCUCAAAAGAGAAUUCAGUCUACAGCCAUUUAAAUGAUCAUUGCUGCUACAGAAGUGCUUUAAGAGAAUUGCCUGAAACAUCUGUAUUAUAUCGGCCACCUGCCAAUCACAGCUUUACUCUUUCAGGUCACUCUGGGGCUGCCUCUUGCAUGUAUUACUAAAUAAAAUGAUCUCUCUUUCUCUCUCUCUCUCUCUUUUCUAAGAAACAAUUAUGUGCACUUUGAUACACAACCUUCUCUAACCAACUAUAUAUCAAGACCCAAAAAUUGAAGAAAAAUAUUGUUUUCUCAUACAGUGAGCAGAUUUUUCAAUCUACUAAUUCUGUGACUUGUCUUGGUGUGCUAGCCUACACCUUCUCUUUGGUUUAGUUUUCCUUUUCUAUAACACUCUGAAUUGCUAAUCUUACUAACACCUAUGAUGUUACCUGAAAUCAAUCUCCCAUAUGUAUGCUGUAUGCUAUGCUAAGACUCCUGAAAUAUACUUACUCUGUGCUUGUGUAUGUGAAUGUUAAUGCAACUAUUACCUAGAGUGAACUUUAAGCUUUAUUGUUGAAUGUAAUUCCAUUAUAUUUCCUUUUGUACACCUGUGAAAAAGUGGAGUAGUGUUUUUUUAACCAUUGUUAAUCAGCUUUUGUGUAUGAAAGACACAGUAAAAUUUCUUUCUUAAAUCAAGAUACUGGUGAUUCAAGGAAUUUUAUUUAUGGUCCAGCCAAGAGCCAUCUCGUGCCAAGACUUCUGCUGGCAAGGGAAUGGAUAAAGCUGUUUUGUUCUAGUAACAAUUUUGGAAUGAAUACUGACAAUAUUCCAUGAGGGUGUGCAAGCACAAAUUUUACCAAUCUGACCUCUUUGAAGUUGCAGAAUGCUUUGAAAUUCUAAUGGUAUCUGAAAUAUCAGCUCAUAGAAAGUAACAAAAUUUGCUGUCACCUUAAAUAAGACAUUUUAAUUUUGUUAUAAUGUACAAUUUAGAAGUUUGAUUAAUUAUAUUAUCUAUUUAGGCAUUAAUAUAAAAGAGGUAGGAGUCUGUUAUUUAAAAAAAGCAUUAAAUUUAAAAAAAAACUGUCUUGUCUACUUUUAGCUUCAUUCUCCCAUAUUUUGAAGGGUGUGUAACUUCAGCUCUGCAGGAUUGCAUGGGGUAAAACUUGUUACCAACACAUGUGAACCAUUGCUACAUUGUAGGUUGUGAUCAUUUUGCCCCACUGAAGCCCAUGUAUCUGACCUUACGUGCCUUUUGAACUAGGAGAAUCGGGCUAAUUUAUUAAUGAUGAUAAUUAUAAUGUAUCUGUACAGCACUUUUUACAUUUGCGAAGUGCUUUCCAAUCCAUGUUAGUUACUAGUUAUUACAGCUGUAAGGAUAAAACACGUCAUGUGGAUUCAUUUUGAAUUGGUGCUAUUGGUAUUUCCUCUGUUAUUGCUAAUAAAUGAAAAUGGUGGUAUGAAA